AGGUGAGCGGCAGACCCGGCACGCAGGUGGGGGCCGGCGGGGUCCGUGGCCAGAGCUGCAGAGAGACAAGGCGGCGGCGGCUGCUGUGCUGGGUGCAGUGAGGAAGAGGCCCUCGGUGGUGCCCAUGGCUGGCCAGGAUCCUGCGCUGAGCACGAGUCACCCGUUCUACGACGUGGCCAGACAUGGCAUUCUGCAGGUGGCAGGGGAUGACCGCUUUGGAAGACGUGUUGUCACGUUCAGCUGCUGCCGGAUGCCACCCUCCCACGAGCUGGACCACCAGCGGCUGCUGGAGUAUUUGAAGUACACACUGGACCAAUACGUUGAGAACGAUUAUACCAUCGUCUAUUUCCACUACGGGCUGAACAGCCGGAACAAGCCUUCCCUGGGCUGGCUCCAGAGCGCAUACAAGGAGUUCGAUAGGAAAGACGGGGAUCUCACUAUGUGGCCCAGGCUGGUCUCGAACUCCAAGCUCAAGCGAUCCUCCCACCUCAGCCUCCCAAAGUACUGGGAUUACAGGUACAAGAAGAACUUGAAGGCCCUCUACGUGGUGCACCCCACCAGCUUCAUCAAGGUCCUGUGGAACAUCUUGAAGCCCCUCAUCAGUCACAAGUUUGGGAAGAAAGUCAUCUAUUUCAACUACCUGAGUGAGCUCCACGAACACCUUAAAUACGACCAGCUGGUCAUCCCUCCCGAAGUUUUGCGGUACGAUGAGAAGCUCCAGAGCCUGCACGAGGGCCGGACGCCGCCUCCCACCAAGACACCACCGCCGCGGCCCCCGCUGCCCACACAGCAGUUUGGCGUCAGUCUGCAAUACCUCAAAGACAAAAAUCAAGGCGAACUCAUCCCCCCUGUGCUGAGGUUCACAGUGACGUACCUGAGAGAGAAAGGCCUGCGCACCGAGGGCCUGUUCCGGAGAUCCGCCAGCGUGCAGACCGUCCGCGAGAUCCAGAGGCUCUACAACCAAGGGAAGCCCGUGAACUUUGACGACUACGGGGACAUUCACAUCCCUGCCGUGAUCCUGAAGACCUUCCUGCGAGAGCUGCCCCAGCCGCUUCUGACCUUCCAGGCCUACGAGCAGAUUCUCGGGAUCACCUGUGUGGAGAGCAGCCUGCGUGUCACUGGCUGCCGCCAGAUCUUACGGAGCCUCCCAGAGCACAACUACGUCGUCCUCCGCUACCUCAUGGGCUUCCUGCAUGCGGUGUCCCGGGAGAGCAUCUUCAACAAAAUGAACAGCUCUAACCUGGCCUGUGUCUUCGGGCUGAAUUUGAUCUGGCCAUCCCAGGGGGUCUCCUCCCUGAGUGCCCUUGUGCCCCUGAACAUGUUCACUGAACUGCUGAUCGAGUACUAUGAAAAGAUCUUCAGCACCCCGGAGGCACCUGGGGAGCACGGCCUGGCACCAUGGGAACAGGGGAGCAGGGCAGCCCCUUUGCAGGAGGCUGUGCCACGGACACAAGCCACGGGCCUCACCAAGCCUACCCUACCUCCGAGUCCCCUGAUGGCAGCCAGAAGACGUCUCUAGUGUUGCGAACACUCUGUAUAUUUCGAGCUACCUCCCACACCUGUCUGUGCACUUGUAUGUUUUGUAAACUUGGCAUCUGUAAAAAUAACCAGCCAUUAGAUGAAUUCAGAACCUUCUAAUGAAAACUCCAUGCCUCUGGUCCUUGGACUCUUGUCCAUGGUUCCUGAGCUGUGGACCGGGAUAGAAUAA